GGACUUGACUUCUCGGACACAGCUAGGGUGGCCCAGGGUGGGAGCUCUCAGUGACUGUGUCUCUGGGUGGUUUCUUGCCCCUGCUGCUGGCCCCACAAAGGGUGUAUUAGCCUGACCUGGGGAGAGUGGGACCCGGGGCUCAGGCCGGGCGUCAGUCUCUGGGGCCUUGCAAUCAGGGAGCGGCAGCAUAGGAGCCGGGGCCCCCUGGACUCUCCGGGCACUGGGGACAGAGAGACGCAGAGAGAAAAGAGAGCCAGAGAGAGUCCAUGGGGGUGUGGGGAGGCAGGCACAGGGACAGGCCAGGCGAGAGCCUUGGGAGGUGGAGGGGGGAGUUGAGAGGGGCCUUCAGGUCUCAGCCCCGCAGGCGCCAGCAUGGCAGCAGGCAGGCCAGCCGGGGGUGGCAGGGCGACCCUGAUACCGAUGUUCCGCCUGCUUCCAGGCUGUGCUCAGGGGUGACCGGGGUAGAUGGACAGAGGCUGCCAGCCCAGUGCAGGAGGGCCACAUCAUCACAGGGACAGUGCCGAGUACCCACUGAGCAGAUAGAUGGUGACGGCCGGUGGUGCAAGGCAUCUGAACCCCGAGGUCCUGAAACCCAAGUCAGCUGCUUAGCCGCCUCUGGGAACCUCAAGGAAGCUCUCCUGCUGCCAAGAUGCCAUCACCACAGACAGACACUCCUGGGCCGGAGCUGCAGAGUCCCAAGGAGGCUGAGGAGCCACAGACUCCAGCUCAGGGCUCCCGGCGAACAAGCAGCAGGAAAGAGCCCAAUGCCCACCGCAAGGAUGGCACAAGGCUGGGCCUGGGCUCCCUGAGGCAGGCCUUCUCCCGGGCCAGCCAGCGGGCUUUGACCCAGGUCUCCAAGGAAGAUACGGGCCUGUUCCGGCGAAGCUCCUGCUCCCUGUUCCGGUCCUUCCGGCAAGCCCUGAAUGACGGCCCAGCUACCGGCCAUUCCCAGGCCACUCCUGAGGUGCCCUCGGGGGUCAUGAAUGGUGUCAGCCAGCAGGCAUCCACUGGGGCAGCGUCUGAGGAACUGAAACCCGAGGCAGAAGGCAAAUCCGUGGCCGACCUCAUUACUGAACGGCAACUGCUGGCGGCCUUCGAACAGCUUCUGCGCCUGGAGACGCUGCUGGUGGCCGAGAAGGCCUCGCGCACCUUUGAGCAGGACCCUACGGCCUUCGCGCGGCGCGCUAUGGACGUGUGCCUGCUUUACGACGGGCUGGCAGCCGAGAUCGGCGCCAUCGUGCGCGAGACGCUGGACAGCGACGGUGUGGACGCGGCCGCGCUGGCCGAGCUGGCCCGCGUGGUGAGCGCGGAGGAGGAAGCCCACCCUUCUCCCCCCGACGACGGCGACUUCCUGCGCACGCCGCGCCGCUGGCGCCAGCACUGGGAGGAGGCGGUGCGGCGAAGCGCUCAGGAGCGCGUGCGGCGGCCGGGCGCGGGGUGGGCCUUCGGGGAGGCGGAGGGCGCGUCGGGUUUGGCCCAGCUUCUGGCCGAGCUGGGUGGCUUGGUUCGCCGCGACCUGCAGAAGGUGCGGCAGGAGGUGCAGCCCGCGUAUGCGGCGGCCGGCUUCCCAGCGUGGGAGGUCUAUCUGCGUGCCUUCCACAGCGCCGUGGCCCAGCGCCUCCAGGAGCUCGCGCGCGACGCCCGCGGCUGCGAGCAGCUCUAUAUCCUGCUGGACUGGGCCGCCAACGUCUACGGCAGUCCUGACUUCCUGGGCGCCCCGGGGCUGGCGCUGCCCGCCGAGCCGCUGCCUCCGCUCCUGGCGCCGGACGUGUGGGCCCGACUGGAGAGCGACUACACCAGCUUCCUGGAGGCCAAGAUCGCAAGCUGCUUCGACAGCAUCUUGCAGCUGGAGCAGAGUCACUGGGCGGCCGCCGAGGUCCCCGAGGUGCUGCAGGGCCUCUACCAGGCGCCGCUGUCCAUGGACGUCCAUAUGCUCGUGGCCGAGCACGUGAAGGCGGCCGGCGCCAUCUCCGCGGAGCUGGAGGCCACCACCCUGCGAAUCUGCACGCGGGCGCUCGGCCUCUUCGUGCCCAGGUUUGAAAAGGCUUUUCUGGCGUCGGAGGCGGUGAGCGAGCCGCACCUGGGCGCCUACAUCAACGCCUGCGAGGAGCUCAGGACCAGUCUUCUCUCCAGGUUCCCAGGAACCCAAGAGGAGCUGGAGAAGCCCCUGGUGACGGCCACCUGCAGCUUCCAGAAGCACUUGCUUCAGGGCUUGCAGCGUGAGUUGCAGCCGCUCUUCAGGGUUGUGUGCACCAGGGACUGGCUGACGCAGGACUGGCUGCAUCCCCUCAUGGACAAGGUGGUGACCUUCGCCGGUCAUCUCCAGCGUGUGGCCCGGCCGCGGGCACAGGAGACUCUGCAGGAGGUGCACCGGUUCGUGGUCCGCGAGUACCUGGCGCGGGCGCUGAGGCCACGGGAGCGGUUCCGGGGCAUGGAGCGCAUGCAUGGCUCCCAGAAGAUGAGCCUGGAUGCCCAGGCCAUCAGCGACACCUUCCAGGGCCUGGGUUCCGAGGCCACAUGGUUGGACCAAGCCAUCCAGUGCGUGGCUGAGAUCCUGGGCGAGACCUACAAAGAUGACAUCCAGCGGCACCUGGAGACUCUUAUCCGGAGCUACCCCGACAUCAGGCGGGACCACAUACUGGCCAUUCUGGCGCUGCGCCGACUGGGCCGCCAGCGGAACCAGCAUCUCUUGCAGCACACUCAAGACCUGCUGAGAGCUGCGGCCGGGGCGGCGGGUGCGGAGGCCCCUCGGGGCCGCGUGCUCUUCGAGGAGAUCAAGGUGCCCAGUGCCAUGGCUGUGCUGAUCACCUGCGUCUAGUUCUCUCUGGCUCGAGGGGGGGCCGGCCGCUGGCAGGGAGCUGUGGUCAGUGGGGGUCAGCCAGGAGCCCAGGGAGUCACUCUGGGCCCUGCCCCCAACUCUGACACUGCAGUUAGGGAAUUUUUGUCGUCAGCAGCCAAGCGCAGCUGUCAGGCCAGAAGGAGCAGCCGUGCAGGAGGCAUUUCAGGCAUCGUUGAGGGGAGUGUUUUGGGGCCGCAGAGCUCUCAAUGCUGCCUAUCGGGCGGGGGGGGGCCUCCCGCCCGACUGUCCAGCUUCACCCUCCAGUCUGAAAGUGAAGAGCAGAGUAUUUAUUUAAAAAAUAAAUGUGAAUUAAAA